GGCAGCGUUCUGGUUUUCUGGAUGGCAGCAGAGGACAGGGAGAUGAUGGAAGCCCGGGGUGCGGGAGAAAGUUGCCCGACCUUCCCCAAGAUGGUGCCUGGUGACUCCAAGUCUGAAGGGAAGCCAAGGGCUUAUCUGGAGGCAGAGUCCCAGAAGCCAGACUCCUCCUAUGACUACUUGGAAGAGAUGGAAGCUUGUGAGGACGGAGGCUGCCAAGGGCCGCUUAAAUCGCUGUCCCCCAAGUCCUGCCGUGCUACCAAAGGCCAGGCUGGCGACGGACCCAAACCCGCAGAGCUGCCCCCGACCCCUGGGACUGAGCGCAAUCCCGAGAUGGAGCUGGAGAAGGUGCGCAUGGAGUUCGAGCUCACGCGGCUCAAGUACCUGCAUGAGAAGAACCAGCGGCAGCGGCAGCACGAGGUGGUGAUGGAGCAGCUGCAGCGGGAGCGGCAGCACGAGGUGGUGAUGGAGCAGCUGCAGCAAGAGGCGGCGCCCCGCCUGUUUUCAGGAGGCCUCCAGAACUUCCUGCUGCCCCAGAACCAGUUUGCCAUGUUCCUGUACUGCUUCAUCUUCAUUCACAUCAUCUAUGUCACCAAGGAGAUGGUCUUCUUUCUCUUCGCCAAGCACUACCUAUUCUGCAUUGCAGCCAUUUUGCUCUGUUUGAUUAAAACUUUCUGGUCAUA